AGAUCGGAGAGGGCACAGGGCCAGGGACUCUGGCCAGACAUAGGCCCAGGUCUGUGGCUGGCCAACUGCGGCUGUGGGGCCUGGCAUGUGUCUCAACAUGGCACUGGAGCUCUACAUGGACCUGCUGUCAGCACCCUGCCGUGCCGUCUACAUCUUCUCGAAGAAGCAUGACAUCCAGUUCAACUUUCAGUUUGUGGAUCUGCUGAAAGGUUCCCUGUUAAGAUGACCCUGAUUGUGUCCGAGAAGCUUCCCUUUGGAUGUCCAGCUGUGUGCUGGGCCUGGCUUCCUUAAAGUGGAGACAGAGUGAGAGCGAUGGGAUUGCGGAUGGGACCCAGGCCCUCAGGGCUUCAGGUCACCACCACAGCAAAGGAUACAUUGACAUCAACCCCCUCAGGAAGCUGCCCAGCCUCAAAGAUGGGAAAUUUAUCUUAAGUGAAAGCAGACAAGAGUACAGAGACCUGGCAGGGCAGGUGGCCCUGGAGUGCAGCCUCCUCUUCCCUCCUCUUCCCAACCCUGGCCAGUUGCUGAUCCCAAAGAUAACAGGGGAGGAAGUUUCAGCUGAGAAGAUGGAGCAUGCAGUGGAAGAGGUGAAGAACAGCCUGCAGCUCUUUGAGGAGUAUUUUCUGCAGGAUAAGAUGUUCAUCACCGGGAACCAAAUCUCACUGGCUGACCUGGUGGCCGUGGUGGAGAUGAUGCAGCCCAUGGCAGCCAACUAUAAUGUCUUCCUCAACAGCUCCAAGCUAGCUGAGUGGCGUAUGCAGGUGGAGCUGAAUAUUGGCUCUGGCCUCUUUAGGGAGGCCCAUGAUCGACUAAUGCAGUUGGCCGACUGGGACUUUUCAACAUUGGAUUCAAUGGUCAAGGAGAAUAUUUCUGAGUUGCUGAAGAAGAGCAGGUGACCCUAGGCGCAGCCUGUCCCGCAGGGCCUGGCUGGCUUAGCAAUCUGAGCCACCUUCCUUAAAGGAAAUGUUAAAAAAAAAAAAACAAAAAAACAAAAAAACAACUGUUCUUUGCCUAAUAAAGAACUGGAACAACCAUCA